AGCGUAGGCUGGCUCCGCCGUAGAGGGGUUGGCAGUGGCGGUCAGCAUGGGCGAUGGGGGCGCCGAGCGCGACCGGGGCCCCGCGCGCCGGGCGGAGUCUGGUGGCGGCGGUGGGCGCUGCGGAGACCGCAGCGGAGCGGGGGACUUGCGAGCUGAUGGCGGUGGCCACAGCCCAACGGAGGUGGCCGGGACCUCAGCCUCCAGUCCCGCAGGCUCCAGGGAGAGUGGAGCCGACAGCGACGGGCAGCCCGGGCCCGGCGAGGCAGACCACUGCCGCCGCAUACUGGUGCGAGAUGCCAAAGGGACAAUUCGGGAAAUUGUCCUGCCUAAGGGCCUGGACCUGGACCGGCCCAAGCGGACACGUACAUCCUUCACUGCCGAGCAGCUGUACCGCCUGGAGAUGGAGUUCCAGCGCUGCCAGUAUGUGGUGGGCCGCGAGCGCACUGAGCUGGCCCGCCAGCUGAACCUCUCCGAGACCCAGAACCAGCCCCAGUCCUGAAACUACCUAGAGAUCCACCCUGAAUCACCUCAUUAGCAUACAACAGUGAUUUAAUGCACAGUGAUGUCUGAGAAUCACUGGCUUAUGGAAAAGUGAGCAAAUCUGACCAGAUGAUGUGAUCACCAUGUUGCUUAAAAGACUUCAUCAACUGCCAGCACUUUAAUAAGUCUGUGAUUAUUAGCCCACCGAGUCAUCACAACAAAACUAUGAGGAAGAGUUAAGAACCCCAUUUUACUGGUGGGGAAACUGAGGCUCCAAGAAGUUAAGUAACUUGACUUAAGUCAUCUAGCUAGUUAAGGGAACCAGAAUUGAAUCAGUGGCUGUCUGACCUCUGAUUCUCCACGAUAGUUUGCUACUAUAUAUUGUCUCCUCCACUAUAUUGUUUGCUACUUCAACCAAAACACUUACCGUGUUGUAACACUUACUGCUUGCCCAUGACCCACCCUGCUAGUGUCUGACAGCCAAGAGGGUCAAAAUGGAGUUUUAUUUAUUUUUGUUUUUUCAGCACCUGGCAAUGCCUGGCUUGCAUCAAAUGCUUGAUAUUUCUGUGUUGCCUGAAUGAAUGACCAGAGUACCAGGGUCCAAGUAGGACAUAAGAGGAUGUGGCUGCAGAGGAAAGGAAGAUGAGAAGCUGGCUCAGGACUCCCCUCCUGCAGCUGGGCUGGAGGACGUUCUCAGGGCCAGGAGCCCAGGAGCCAGGUGGAGAACAAACUGCCAAGUCCCAAUAUCCCCCCGGGAUGCCCACCUAGCUUGGGUAAGAGCUGCUCCAGCCCUUCAGCAUUGUCCUCAGCCUCAUGCUUGAUGCCUCUGCCUCAGAUGGCUUCUUCCAGAACAGCACGAUAGAUGGUACCUUCCUAGUGCAGAUUACAAAAACCAAGCCAUCCUAGAUACACAGAUACCACUCACCUCAGAUUAAGUAUGGGCCCAUGGUCACAGAAAACAGUCUUCAAAAGAUGAAUGCCAUUUCCAGAUCAACAAUGAAUCCUGGAAUUUGAUAUUGACCAUGAGCCCAAAGAAGCUGGUGGAUAAUCUCCUGGAAAAUUCCUCUGUAGUCCUGGCAGCCAAGUGGAAACUGUGCCCAUCUCCUGGUGCGCGGCCAUGGAUCACAGUGUGGCCCAGAAAGAAAUCAGGGAGGGGGCAGUGCCAUGGGUCACAGUGUGGCCCAGCAAGAGAUCGCGGAGGGGGGCGGGGCAGCCACCAAGCACUCACUGAGUCCCAGGGAGUCAAGAUGGCAGCCUCCAGGAGGCCACACAGGACCCUGAGAAAACAGAGGAGGGAGACAGCCCAGAAGGUGCACUGGGCAGGUGAGGGGAGAGGCACAGCUGCGGAGGUGUGCUGGCCCCGCCACCCUGUGAAGUCGGCUAGGAAUGGUUUCCCAGAAGUGGAUAAGGACCGAUCACUUUGGAUUUAACCUUGAGAAGAGGAUGAACCUGAGAUGGAAAUGAAGGUUUCCUGGGGCAGGAGGGACACAUUCAGAGGGCUCUGAGCCUGUCUGUUCUUCAGAAAGACAGAGAGACAACAUUUGCAGGGCCCUGUGAACCUACCCGCUAGGGCCUGAAGGGCCUGAUAGGCUUGGUGGGCCUGAUGGGCUUGAUGGUGGGAAGUAGAGAGUUGACCCUUCUUACUCUCACCCUUGAAGUUUGCAAUGCUGGGAAGCACAUUAGAUUCACCCACAGAGCUUUAGAAGAAUACCCAGGCCUCAGCCCCAUUCCCUAGAGAUUCUGAUUUAAUAUGGGUGAGGCAUGAGGCCCGGACAUCAUCCCAGAAAAUUCCAGUGUGCGGCCAAGGUUGAGAAUUCCUGACCUAGCCCAUAUGUGGCCAAGAAACAAGCACCCCUGGUCCCAGCCCCUGCUCCAUCUGCCUCUGACUUCUCCUCUCCUAGGGUCCAGGCUCACCUUCUCAGGAGACGCCCAAACCCAGCACCAGCCCACACCCGCCUCUCCUUGCUACACCCAGAGCUGCAGGAAGAUGGGAUAUGUGGGAGAGCACCUUGUAAAUGCCUGGUCAUUCCUCAUCUGUCACACCCCAUUACUGCCACUCCCUGAGUACGAAUUGCCCUCUGUUUUUUGGGAAUGAGUUAGUGCCACUCCCCCACUAGACCCUCAGCUUCCCAAGGACUGGAGUCAUGACAUCUGUGUCUCCUCUCCCUCUAGUUCAGAAACAGAGCUAGAAACAGAGAAAGCCAGCGAUAAAUAACUAUUCACAUUUCCUGUGGGCCAGGCGUGAUGCCAAGCUCCCUAAAUGGGUUUUCUUCUUUCAUCUCUGCAAUAGCCAAGUAUUAUUGUCCCCAUUUUAAAGAUAAGACACUGAGGCUCAGGGGUUCCUGGAGGUGGCCUGGCCUCAGGUCCUAGGACGGGGAGGUGCUGGCUUGGCUAAGAGGUCAGGAAGCUUCCCAGCAGGGAGGGGGAAUGCAGCAGUGUGCAGCGCUAUGGUCCUUGAGGAUCUGGUGAGACUCCUUCCCUCAGCAGUCAGAUUCCAGAGGUGACAAAUGGGAAAGGGUUUUCUUCUUUCCAGUCAUUGCCUUCAGCUAGACUUGGCUGAAUCUUCCUUGACCAUCCCUUACUGAUAUCUUCUUCAAAUGUCCCCUCUUCAGGGAGGCUGUAUGUGCCAUUCCAUUAACAAAACAGUCACCCCCCUCCUUCCUUUCUGCUAUCCUGCCACCUUUCUCUAAAGCAGUGCCCCCCAGAGUAUGGCCCUUGGGCCACUGCCAGCCCAUAAACUGUUACCUGUCUAUGACAUGGUAAGUAUAGAAAUAAAGAAUAGGUAUUUAGAAAAGGCCUGGAGCGGUGGCUCAUGCCUGUAAUCCCAGCACUUUAGGAGGCCGAGGUGGGCAGAUCACGAGGUCAGGAGUUCGAGACCAGCCUGGCCAACAUGGUGAAACCCUGUCUCUAGCAAAAAUACAAAAAUUAGUUGGGUGUGAUGGCACACGCCUAUAAUCCCAGCUACUCAGGAGGCUGAGGCAGGAGACUCACUUGAACCCCGGAGGUGGAAGUUGCAGUGAGCCGAGAUCAUGCCACUGCACUCCAGCCUGGGCUACAGAGUGAGACUCCAUCUCAAAAAAAAAAAACAAUGUAUAUAGCAAUCUUUCCAGUAAUUCAUUUUAAUUGUAUUUUUUAAAGUAUUGGUCCUCAACAAAAUUGGACACUUUAUAAAGUGGUCCUCACCUCAAAUCAUUUGAGAAACACGGCUCAAAGCCCUUGCUGCCAAUUGACAGACAGGCUUGUUUGUGUUUGUUGUUCAUCCUCUGCCUCCCCAACUCCACCGCCCACUCCACGUGGCAAGGAUUCACUGGGCUUUGUUCACUGCUGAUUCCCUGGGCCUCAAUGUAUAUCUGGUGAGUGAAUGAAUGGAUAAAUGAAGCAAUCAACCUCAAGUAGGUCUCAUAACUUUCUGGUCACUUUUGAUUAUUGAAUCUGCAUCCGCCAGGUGCGGUGGUGUGCACCUGUAGUCCCAGAACUUGGGAGGCUGAGGCAAGAGGAUCACUUGAGGCCAGGAUUUUGAGGCUGCAGUGAGCUCUCAUGACACUAGUGUACUGCAGCCCAGGCAGAAAACCAACACUUUGUCUCUAAAAACAAAAAUAAAGAAAUAAACUCAAUCCAAUGUCCUUCAAAACACCAACUCACAUCUAGUUUAAAUCUCAUCUUCUCCUGAAGCCCCACACCUGCUUCCCCACUCAGAACAGCCUUGACUCACUGCUUGCCAGCAAGGUUUGAGGUUUGAGGAAAGCACAUCUCACAUAGGAGCAUGAACACCCAGUCAUCCUGCUGAAGAACUACAAAAGGACCCCUGCCCACUCUUUACCUCCUCCCAGUGCAGCCUCUGGAGGGGAUUGUGAUCUGUCUCAGUCACUUGCUCCCUCUUCCCCCAACAGCCACCUCCUCCAGGAUCAGACGACAGGGGGUGGCUUCAAGGAGGCAGAGAUCUUUUUAAAAGACUGGACAUCUUCUGGUGUGAGGAGGGGAAGCACCAAGGCCUCACUUUCUGAAGGCCUUUGCUGAAGGGCCAGUCACUCCUAGCAGGUGGUGAUGUCUGGCAUGGCCCAGGUGGCCCAGUCUGUCUUGGCUCUGCCUGUCUUCUUAACCUGGGCAGCCCUCUGGCUCAAGCCUUCUCCUCCACCCAUCUCUUGGCAACUUCUCAAAACCACAGCAGUUGCUGGACUAUUAAAUCUUCCAAAAGCUGGAAGGAA